AUGACGGCAGAAAGCUCCCGCCCCACCACGCUGAUGACGGCAGAAAGCUCCCGCCCCACCACGCUGAUGAUGGCACUCUCGUUGGGUGGCACUGCUGCGCACAGCCUGUGGCUAGACGAGGUUCCCGUGGGUUUGCCUGGAGGCGUUGCUGCACGCAGCCUGUGGCUAGACGAGGUUCACGUGGGUUUGCCUGGAGGCGUUGCUGCGCGCGGCCUGUGGCUAGACGAGGUUCACGUGGGUUUGCCUGGAGGCAUUGCUGCACACGGCCUGUGGCUAGACGAGGUUCACGUGGGUUUGCCUGGAGGCGUUGCUGCGCGCGGCCUGUGGCUAGACGAGGUUCACGUGGGUUUGCCUGGAGGCGUUGCUGCGCGCGGCCUGUGGCUGGACGAGGUUCACGUGGGUUUGCCUGGAGGCGUUGCUGCGCGCGGCCUGUGGCUAGACGAGGUUCACGUGGGUUUACCUGGAGGCGUUGCUGCGCACGGCCUGUGGCUGGACGAGGUUCACGUGGGUUUGCCUGGAGGCGUUGCUGCGCGCGGCCUGUGGCUAGACGAGGUUCACGUGGGUUUGCCUGGAGGCGUUGCUGCGCGCGGCCUGUGGCUAGACGAGGUUCACGUGGGUUUGCCUGGAGGCGUUGCUGCGCGCGGCCUGUGGCUAGACGAGGUUCACGUGGGUUUGCCUGGAGGCGUUGCUGCGCGCGGCCUGUGGCUAGACGAGGUUCACGUGGGUUUGCCUGGAGGCGUUGCUGCGCGCGGCCUGUGGCUAGACGAGGUUCACGUGGGUUUGCCUGGAGGCGUUGCUGCGCGCGGCCUGUGGCUAGACGAGGUUCACGUGGGUUUGCCUGGAGGCGUUGCUGCGCGCGGCCUGUGGCUAGACGAGGUUCACGUGGGUUUGCCUGGAGGCGUUGCUGCGCGCGGCCUGUGGCUGGACGAGGUUCACGUGGGUUUGCCUGGAGGCGUUGCUGCGCGCGGCCUGUGGCUGGACGAGGUUCACGUGGGUUUGCCUGGAGGCGUUGCUGCGCGCGGCCUGUGGCUGGACGAGGUUCACGUGGGUUUGCCUGGAGGCGUUGCUGCGCGCGGCCUGUGGCUAGACGAGGUUCACGUGGGUUUGCCUGGAGGCGUUGCUGCGCGCGGCCUGUGGCUGGACGAGGUUCACGUGGGUUUACCUGGAGGCGUUGCUGCGCGCGGCCUGUGGCUGGACGAGGUUCACGUGGGUUUUGCUGUGAAGAGGUCUGUCCAGAAGCGGGGGUAGAGAAAGGGUGAUUUUUAUCGCAGAACAAGUCAUGUUGUUUUAAUCUCACCAGAAGUUUCAUCUAAUUUGAAAUAGAAAAAGACCAAGCACUACAGAUUGAAGCUGGGUGCCUGAUGGACACCUGCUCGUGUGCUUCUCUGUAAGUAUUUGCAUUGUCGCAGCUGCAAGCACCCAUUUCGCUGAGAAUCACUGUUGCCUCCAUGGGGUCCUGUCCUAUGGACGACCCCUGUCUAGUUGGGAACUUGGUGCCAGGAGCUCAACUUGCUCCAAUGCUUCCCAUCCUACUAAGUUCUACGCUGACUACAGUGGUAGGUAACGUCUGUUUUCCUGCAGUGCUUAAAUAUUGUUUCUACCUCCACCUUCGGCAGCUAUGUGGCAGACAUUUAAUCAUUGUUAGGCAAAAAAGACCUAAACGUACUCUGUUAGCUACUGCACCCUGCCUGGAUUCCCCAGGCCACAUGUCUUAGUUAGCCCCACACAGCUUCAGAUAUUGUUAUUGCUUCUAUCCAUUCUGCUAAACUGAGCCAUGGUUAAUAAAAGAUGAGAAUUGGCAAUUUCCAAGUUUCUAAGAGUUUAAAGUUAUAGGAAAUAAAAGACAUGAUGUAUUCCUCAGAGUAGGCUCACUAUUGUAACAACGCCUCCGAAUUUUAGUAGCUUACCAAAAUAAGAACGUAUUGUUCACUUGCAUGACUGUCAAACCUAGGCCAGAUGAGGGCUGUGCUCCACAACACCGCCCAGGAAUCUGGGAUCCUCCCCUGGGCUCCAGUAGCUCCAUGGACAUCUGCAGGUAGAAUAUAAACAAGGAAGCUGGGAGGAACUGGUGAGAUUUCAGAGGAGGCCUAGAGGUGGUGGCCAUCACUCUCCCUCCCAGUCUCCUGGCCAGGACUUGGUCACACAGCUGCACCUCACAGCGAGGGGCUGGGGAACGCGGCCUCACCCCGUGUCCAGGAAGAGGAGUGACCUGCCAUGGUGAGAAUCUCCGCUCCUGAAGAGCACAUGAUUAGUCAUUUACACGUCCUGAUGUUGUUGCUCAGGGUCUCCUCCUACCAGGGGAGACAGUGGAAAACUGUGUGCAUUGCUCACAGUGAGGAAGCUGGUUCCUUGGCUGGUCUGUGGGUCACAUUGCUCAUCUUCAUGGGGACAGCGGCCACUCUUCACCAUGCUUCCUGUUGCUGGAUUGCAAUGGGAGCCAUGCCAUCGAUGCUUUGGGCAAAAUAGCUCAUGUAUGGCUCCUCGUCAGCUGCAUGCAGUGGCACAGAUGCACCAUGAAGCUUGCAGUUGGGUGUCUGCACCUCUCAAAACCAUUUCCAGCUGGACAAGCAGGCCUCUUGGUGCUAAUGCACCUGUGAAAGGCAAAGACCCUCUCAUCAUUCCAUGAGCCAUAUGCUGGCUCUAUGUUUUUAUGCCUGUCUCCCAUAACAGGUGACAUUGUUGAGAAUGAGUAGCGGGGGGUGUCCGAUAGCUGUUACUUUGAAGUAAAAGGAAUUCACUGAUCCAGCUGCAGUGGGUCCCUAAAGCAAGGGCUGCUUAACACGUAUACUCAGGUUGCAUGAUGGCCGUGGAGUACACUGGACUCAGCACCAGGACCCCAUCUCUCAUCACCAGCUGUGUGUACGCCUUGGUGAGCUCCUUAAAUCUAAACACGUGAGUAUCCUUAUUUGUCAAAAGAGGAUUCAAAUUUUAACCCUGCAUAACCAAAAAUACAGGAAUUACUUAAUGAAGGGGUUCUUGAGAAGCGAUAAACUGAAAGGUAAGUCAAAGCCCCAUGGCAAAUGCAAAUGGCUUGAAAAUGCAGGAAAUGCUUUCAUCCUGGAACAUUUGCUGUUCUACCCAAGUCAGGUCUGUGUCUCUGGAGGUGCACACGGAGCUGUCCCUGGUGGCAGCCUCUGCCAAGGACUGUGUGGCCCCGGGGGCAGCCUCUGCUGAGUAUUGUGUGUUCCUGGUGGCAGCCUCUGCUGAGUGUUGUGUGUUCCUGGUGGCAGCCUCUGCCAAGGACUGUGUGGCCGCGGGGGCAGCUUCUGCCGAGUGUUGUGUGUUCCUGGUGGCAGCCUCUGCUGAGUGUUGUAUUGCUGGUGGCAGCUUCUGCCGACGGCUGCGUGGCCCAAGUGUGCGUCCUGCCUUUUCCUGACUUCCUCUCUCUACUUCCCACUCUCACCCGGCACAUGAUAAAAUGUAAUCUACAUGAAUAUUAGGAUUUGGAUUUCUAUCUGGACACGUGAUUUACCUAUUAAUCAGACACCAACCACAUGAAUGAUUAUUAGAGGAAUAUUUAACAAAAGCUACAUAAAAACAGUUUUUGAAACUAUUUGGACUUCACUUCUCAUAACAUUCUUAAAAACCAAAGUUCAGUGUGUCUUCCAAAAUGAAGAAAAAUUACCCUGUUUUACCAAUGGUUUUGCGUCGCUAAUAUCAUAAAAUGAAGGAUGAGUUUUCAAGCCUGAAAGACAGUGUAUUUACUAAACAAUUUCUUAAUAAAUUCAUUUAUUCAUGCA